ACACCCGAGAAAGUUUCAGCCAAACUUCGGGCGGCGGCUGAGGCGGCGGCCGAGGAGCGGCGGACUCGGGGCGCGGGGAGUCGAGGCAUUUGCGCUGGGCUUCGGAGCGUAGCGCCAGGGCCUGAGCCUUUGAAGCAGGAGGAGGGGAGGAGAGAGUGGGGCUCCUCUAUCGGGACCCCCUCCCCAUGUGGAUCUGCCCAGGCGGCCGCGGCGGCGGCGGCGGAGGAGGCGACCGAGAAGAUACCCGCCCUGCGCCCCGCUCUGCUGUGGGCGCUGCUGGCGCUCUGGCUGUGCUGCGCGACCCCCGCGCAUGCAUUGCAGUGUCGAGAUGGCUAUGAACCCUGUGUAAAUGAAGGAAUGUGUGUUACCUACCACAAUGGCACAGGAUACUGCAAAUGUCCAGAAGGCUUCUUGGGGGAAUAUUGUCAACAUCGAGACCCCUGUGAGAAGAACCGCUGCCAGAAUGGUGGGACUUGUGUGGCCCAGGCCAUGCUGGGGAAAGCCACGUGCCGAUGUGCCUCAGGGUUUACAGGAGAGGACUGCCAGUACUCGACAUCUCAUCCAUGCUUUGUGUCUCGACCUUGCCUGAAUGGCGGCACAUGCCAUAUGCUCAGCCGGGAUACCUAUGAGUGCACCUGUCAAGUCGGGUUUACAGGUAAGGAGUGCCAAUGGACCGAUGCCUGCCUGUCUCAUCCCUGUGCAAAUGGAAGUACCUGUACCACUGUGGCCAACCAGUUCUCCUGCAAAUGCCUCACAGGCUUCACAGGGCAGAAGUGUGAGACUGAUGUCAAUGAGUGUGACAUUCCAGGACACUGCCAGCAUGGUGGCACCUGCCUCAACCUGCCUGGUUCCUACCAGUGCCAGUGCCUUCAGGGCUUCACAGGCCAGUACUGUGACAGCCUGUAUGUGCCCUGUGCACCCUCGCCUUGUGUCAAUGGAGGCACCUGUCGGCAGACUGGUGACUUCACUUUUGAGUGCAACUGCCUUCCAGGUAAGGAGCUCCCUAGUGUCCCAGGAUUAGGGGACAAACCCCUAGCACAGGAGGUAGUGGGUGUGGCUCAAUUGCUUUUUUUAGGAAGCGCAAGGAAAAAGGGAAGUGAGAAUUUUGUGUGGGGUGGGUUGCUAGUGAGGGAGGAGUUUUAUGGGCCCACUGUGGUCCAUAAACUGAGCAGGGGAUAAUUUAGCAUGUCAGGGUUUAUGAUGAUGAGUGGCUAGAAAAUUGUUUAUUGUCCCUUUUGUAGAAACAGUGAGAAGAGGAACAGAGCUCUGGGAAAGAGACAGGGAAGUCUGGAAUGGAAAAGAACACGAUGAGAAUUAGACACUGGAAAAUAUGUAUGUGUGGUUAAUAAAGUGCUUUAAACUGAAUUGACAUUAACAGUGGGUGAUCAACUUUACUAUGUGCUUGUGCUUUUGCUUUUGAUGGAGUAAUUCAUUGUUUUCUUAUCCACCUAAAUGCACCCAGCUGCCCUUGAUUUUCUCUGGGCUACUGGCCUUCACAACCCUCUCCCAUGUACCCUCUCUGACUUUGGGGUAACCCUCCCCUAACUUAAAGCUAGAGAAUUCUGAAACUGAGGAGGGGAUCCUCUGUUAAUCAGUGAGCACUUUUUGAUGAGCUGAUAGAUGAUAUAUGAGAGACUAUGCGUGGCACAAUACUUUGUUACACUCUUCACUGAUACAAGUGUUCUAGAGUGUACACACAACCCAAAGAUAGAAAUAAAAAGAGGAGCAGUGUCGGGGAGCUUGGGGCCUGGUGUUCCAUGGAGAGGGAGAAAGGAACAAGCUUGACCAAUUCAUUCAACUCCUUAUAAAAAUGAUGAGGAGGCUGAAAACCAAGAAUUUUGAUUGGGAACAGAAUACAAGCAGCUGAAUCAGAUGAAUUACUAAGCAACAAAGAUCCUGUUUUUAUACAAAUAUCCUUAGUACAAAAACAAAAGAAGGAAAACUGUAGGGGGGAGUAAUGUGCUAAGUAAGCAGAAUUGCCUCAAAAAGAAGUUGUUCUAGUUACUCUUUCAGAGUGGGAAUCUUAGAUUCUGGUAUUGUGGAUAUGGUUCACAUAUAAUGGGAUUGUGUGUUUUAUUUUGGAGGGAUUAAAGGUCAUAGUUUGGUCCUCAGUAUAAAAUCAACUGGUAAUUUAUUCAUUUCAUUUGGUAAAAAUGUAUUGACUGCCUGCUAUGUUCUAGGCACCAUGCUAUGUAUUUGGAAUACAGCUAUACAAAGCAUUGUCACAUAAUUGAAAUGAAAAUUUUAUAUUAUUUAAGUCACAAGAACAAGCUAUUUAAUUAUAUUACUUUUAGUUUCUCUUUUAAUAAAGAAUAGAUAAUGCUAUCAUUCUAGAUACUAAAUAAGUAUUUUCUUAACAUAAUAUUACUAUCCACUUUAUCUUGUAGAAGAAAUAACUAAAAUACAUCUGUCUUCACUCCUGUAUUUGUUUGCAUUUUAAGGAUUAAAGACAGAAAUAGAAAUGUAAACAACUUUAUUUUGAAAAUAUUUCAACACUGCAAAUAUCUCUGGGUCUGAUAUUCUAGUAAUCUAAUUGGCUAGUAAUUGAUGUUAGUGUGAUUUAUUGUUGAAGGCUAAAUGUGUUUUUCAGUUUCAAGAAAAUUGCUUUUAAUAAUUGCCUAGAACAAGAGGUUGAUUUGGCAGCAAGAUGUUGACGGGAAGUUAGAGAAGUCAAUAAAGGAAGUUUUUAGCUGAGAGAGAGUGAUUAUUCACUCCCAUAGCCUCUGCAUUGUUAUCCAUUAGCCACGAUAAGAACCUUAGGGAAUUCUGAGAGUGUGUCCAGGAAAGGAUCUGUCAAACUAGAAUAGUAUCUCCUCCUUGAGAAAGGAAAUAACCAAGGAUUCCGCAGCUGAGAGGCUGCCAGGGCUAGUGAAAUAGAGUAAGGAAAUCUUGGCUGUCUCUUAUUCUCUGGUUGUAGUUUAACGCAAGACACUUAUUUACUCACUGAUGGUGUGUGUGUGUGUGGGAGGGGAGAUUAGCAUGAGGGGUGGGAAUGGGGAGAUUCGAUGAAGAGAAAACUAACAUUUUUUUGGUGACUCAGGAACUGUGCCAGGUACUUCCAUGCUUAUUAGCUCAAUUACACAAAAAUCUUGGGACCAGGUAUUAUUUUUCAAGUCUUCCCACAUGAAGUAACUGAAGUUUGGAGAUGUUAAGUGAUUCACCCAAAGUUGUACAGCUAAUAUGUGGUUAGGCUGGGUCCUGAAACCGAGGCAGUUUAUUUUCAAAGCCUUUGCUUUGUGCAUCUUACUGCGCCACAUUGCACUGCACAUCUGCUUCCUGAAAGCACUUUGUAGGUGUGUAAAACUUUUCGUUAAAUGCUUUAAGCUGUUUGGGUUAAAAAUAUAUGUUCAUGUUAUAAGAAAACCAAGACACUCCUAAUUAUAAUCAAAUAGUACUUGUUACAUAUCAAUAUGUGUGUGUGUGUGUGUGUGUGUGUGUGUGUGUGUGUGUGUGUGUGUGUGUGUAUGGCGUUGUGCAGAUGUUUAAAAGUAGUUACAUAGACUAGUUCUUGCUUUUCAGGGUCCCAUAAUCUAAACCAGAUGACUUCAGCUUUGGAUAAAUAUAUAGAAGGAAAUUUAAAGAGAAUUCAAAACAAUAGAUGAUGCAGUGACACUGUGAAUAAAUGUUAUUUAUACAGUUUGUAAGAUUUCAUGCUCAUUGUUCAUAUGUCCCAGGUGGAGUUCAGAAAAUAUUCUCUUCAUUUCCACAAAGGGGAAUAGUGCCUGGAGAUGGUUUUCUUUUAAAAAGUCCUUUUCAUAAUGCAGUGCCCUUCCUUCCAUUGCCCUUCAUUCCAUUGCUUCCCAUGCUUGUCAAGAGACUAAAAUGUUACUUAUAGUAAUAGUCACUAUCUCAAUGUAAAUAGCACCCUUAUUUGAUGAGAAUUAUUAUUUCAGUUCUAAAAAUGGGGAAACAAAGUCAGCAGGAGGCAAAGUAGCUUGUUAAAGUAUUCUGCAACUUUCAAAUGGUUGCUUCCACUGCAUUUCACGUCUUGGCACUUCUAAUUGAGGGUUACUCUAACCACCCUAUUUAAAAUUGUAACUGUCCCCCACCCCCUUAAUUACUAACCCUGGUCUACUUUUUGUUUUCUUUUUCUGUAACUCUUAUCUUCUUACUAUAUAAUUUAUACUAUAUAAUUUACUUCAUUAUGUCUAUUGUUCAUUGUCUGUCUUUUCCAAAUUCUACUGCCUCUUACCCUCUCCAGAAUGAAAACUAGUAUCUUUGUUUUUGUUUACUGAUGUAACCCAAACACCUACAAACAGUGCCCAGUAUAUACUAGGCCCACAAAUAUAUAUUGGCUGACUGACUGUAUGGUUUAGUAUCAUGUCAUAGUAUUGAGACUGUAACUUUGGUCUUCUCAUUUUCUUCUUUGUAUUGUGCGUCCUAGACUUAGUUUGGCCUCUCCUUUUGUCCUUGUAUACUCUAAUACUGGAUAAGAAUUUUGGAGUCUUUUUCAACUCUGAGUCAGUGAAUGCCACAUAACUUAGUGACUAUAUUUAAAUGGUUAAUUUACAAUUUUUUCCCUGCAAAGGAUACUGUAGUCACUGUGAGUAUUUUAGUAUUAUUGUAGGACUCAAGAGGGAAUUAAAACUACAAAAAUGACUCCUCUUGUAUGACACAGAAAGAAAUGUUUCUUCACAGAGGGAGGAGAAAAAUAUCUUCAAGAGAGAACUAAUAGAAUCAAAUCAAUGAACCAUGUCUCAUCUUUUUGGAUAAGUAACUGUUAGUAAUCCAGACACUUCAUGAGCUUUCAUUAUGUAAAGUCUUUAGCAGAAGCUAAAGGAGGGGCACCAACCACAGUAAUUUUAACUUAAGAACAAAAUGGAGCAUGAAAAUAAAUUAUUAAAUCAUUUACUCCCACUAUUUUUGGGUUAGGGCCAAUAAUGGGGAGAGAAAGAGGUAGACUAGUUUUGUGUUUGUGGCUAUUUUAAUAGAGUAGCACAAGUAAUCAAAAAACAGUAGGCUGUUUUGAAUUUACUGGCUGUCCCUUAUGAGUUCACAGUUAGAUUGGACUGUCCUCAAUGUACUUUCUUUUUUUUCUUUCUUUCCCACAUCUCUUUAUUUCUCUGAUUUUGUUUAAACUUCAUAAAGAGCUCUCUGAUCUUUCCUUUCCAAACAAUGAAGGUUUAUCCUUUGUAAACUACCUCUGUACUCCACAGGCUGAUGAUAUGUGAUAUCCCUAUAUCAUUAAAGUAAAGCCUAAGCACAUUCUAUGGCUUUUGUGUCUACUCUGUUGUUGCUGAGCUUAUGAACUAUUAGAAAUAACUCCCUCUUGCAUUUUCACACAUGGGGAAUGUGAUGUUCUCUUGGGUAUUAUGCUAAUCAUAUUUUGGCAGGUUUCUCUGGAGCAGAUGCAGAAAUGAUCAUACCACUUUCCAGGGUGUAUUAUUUUAGCUCCUUUGACUUGGGCCCUAAGUCUGUUUUACCUGAUGUUCCUGAAAGAUGUUCCUGAUGUCCUUCACUGUUCUUUCAUGCUGGAUGUUCUUGCCUAUGCUGCCUCCUCAGCUAUCACCCUCUCUUCCCCUUUUUAAUGUAGAACUCAUUCUUAAUGAUUUGUCAAAGGCACCCUAUUUCACUGAAAUGCCUUCUAUAUUCCCUACCCUCCAAGUGGAUUGUAGACCUUCUAAGGUCUUUUGACAUCUGCAUAUCUCUAGCACAGCACUUAUCACGGUGAUUAUUUAUCUGUUCAUCUUUCCAAGUAGACACUCUCAUUUUAACUCCCUACCCUAGUCGCCAGCAUCCCCAGCAUAGUGCCUGUCAUAAAAUGGUGCCACAAUGAAAAUUUGAAAAAUGAAUGAACGUGAUAAACAUAGAUGAGAAUCCUAUAUUCUACAAUUUUUUAAAUGUACUGAAAUUAUUCUUUUUGAAUCCUCCUAUUUAUUUCUGUGACUUCUUUGAUGACAAAGUUAGAAAAAAGUGGAGGUCAGUAGGGAGAUAUGAAGGGACGCAGGUGGAAGCAGUGAGCCUGGGCGGGUGAUGGAGUGGGAGAUACGUGGCACAGGGGUCAGUGAGUUAAUCUGGGCUCAUUCAGAGAAUGGAAGGUGUGUGCCAAGAAAACUGGUUGGAUAGGGAUAGGUCAGGGAUUCCCUCUUGCAUUCUCACACUUGGGGGCAUGUGUCAUUUUCUUUUCUUUUCUUUUUUUUUUUUUUUUUUUUUGAGACGGAGCAUCGCUCUUUCUCCCAGGCUGGAGUGCAAUGGUGCUAUCUCGGCUCACUGCAACCUCCACCUCCCGGGUUCAAGCUAUUCUCAUGUCUCAGCCUUCCAAGUAGCUGGGACUACAGGUGCCUGCCACCAUGCUCAGCUAAUUUUUGUAUUUUUAGUAGAGAUGGGGUUUCACCAUGUUGGUCAGGUUGGCCUCGAACUCCUGAUCUCAGGUGAUCCACCUGCCUCGGCUUCUCAAAGUGCUGGGAUUCCAGGCAUGAGCCACCAUGCCUGGCCGCAUGUGUCAUUUUCUUGGGUGUUAUACUGAUCGUAUAUUUGCAGGUUUGCUUUUGUGACAGACUUCUUCUGGGGGAAAAAAAGUAUCCUUCUAUCUUUUUACUUUUGUCCAGUUCCAGGUAUCCCUGUUUUUUUCUUCACUCUUCCUUCCUUGUUCAUGGGAGUUUUUCUUGAGGACUUCAAGCCCAGCUUCGGAGAAUCCUGGUUGUGUCAUCUCAUCUCCUUUCUGCUCUCUUCUCUACCUAGCCUUUCCACCCUCACACCUCCCGGGGUCUGAAAAUGGAAAGAUAAGGGUGUUUCCCUGAAAGUUGCUCUUCUGUGUGGGGAUGACAGGUUCUAAAGACUCUUUUCUGGUCCCUGCCCUCAUUGCCAUGAUUAAUCAGUUAAGUGGCCCGAGGUUUUAUAACAGCACAGUCUUAAAAUGCUUCUCCCAAGUUUAAUUUCUCUCCAUUUGACCUUUUAAGGAUGUGAAUUGGCUUUAAGCAGUAGACUCCCUUUAGUACGGUGCUGUGAGCCUCUCAGUGAAUCUGCUACAUCCAUUCCACCCACGGGUCUGGAAACUUGUCUGUUUACCUUUCCCUAAAAACCUAAGAUAUAUUUUUAAGAAGUGCCUUGUAACUUUUCAUAUAGCCUUUCCCCUACUUUGGGUAGACUGUUUCUUACAGGAAUUUGGUAGAUCUUUCCAAAGAGAAUUCUGUAUCUGUAUUUUUAAAGCAUAAAUCCUGUCAACUUUGGAGGAGAACUGAUUUGGCUUGAGUUUUCUCAGACAUGGGAACUUUUGACCUAAGUUUGUAUUUUACAUUGUUGAAAGGGAACUCCGGGAUCCCAGAAAACAUAUGGACUGCAAUUGGGUAAAGUUUCUGUUCCAGAAAUGCCUCUUCUGGACAUUUCAUACAAAUGGAAACAUGCAGCAUGUAGUAAUUUAUGACAGCUUCUUUCACUUAGCAUGAGGUUUUCAAAGUUCAUUGAUGUGGUAGCAUUUGUCAGUACUCUGUGCCUUUUUAUGGCUGAAUAAUAUUUUAUCAUAUGGAUUUACCACAUUUUAUCAUUUUAUUUAUCCAUCAUCAGUUGAUUGACAUUUGAGUUGCUUCUACUUUUUGAGUAUUAUCAAUAAUUCUGUUAUGAACAUUCUUGUAUAAUUUUUUGGUAGACAUUUAUCUUCAUAUUUCUUGGAUAUAUACCUAGGAGCAGAAUUGCUGCGUCAGAUGGUAAUGCUGUUUAACCUUUUCAGGAACUGUCAGACUGUUCUGAAGUGGGUACAUUAUUUUACAUUCCAACCAGCAGUGUAUGAGAAUUCCAGUUUCUCCACAUCCUCAUCAACAGUUGUUAUUGUCUGUCUUUUUUAUUAUAUUCAUCUGUAAUGUGAAGUGUUUAUCUCAUUGUGGUUUUGAUUUACAUUUCCCUGAUGGUUGAUGAUUUUCAACAUCUUUUCAUAUACUUAUUAGUCAUUAUGUAUCUUCUUUGGAGAAUGUCUGUUCAGAUCCUUUACCUACUUUAUAAUUGGUUUAUCUUUUUAAUAUUGAACUGUAAUAGUUUUUAAAAAAUAUAUCCUAAAUACAAGUCUCUUAUCAGAUAAUAUGAUUUGCAGAUAUUUUCUGUCAUUCUAUGUACUGUCUUUUCACAUUCUUGAUGAUAUACUUUUCAGCCCAAAUGUUUUUAACUUGAUGGAAUACAAUUUAUUUUUUCUUUUGUUGCUUGUGCUUUCAGUCAUAUUUGUGAAAACUUUGCUUAUCCCACAUUACAAAGAUUUACUAUUUCUAAGUGAUUUAUAAUUUUACCACCUACCUUUAGGUCUCUGAUCCAUUUUGAGUUAAUUUUUAUGUGCGAGGAGGGAGUCUAACUUGAUUCUUUUACAUGUGGAUAUUUAGUUGUCCCAGGACCAUUUGUUGAAUUAAGUGCCCAGAACAAGUACAUCUAUAUAUAGAGAAAGUAGAUUAGUGGUUGUCAGAGACUGUAAGAAGUGGGGAAUUGGAGAGUGACUGCCCAUAGGUACAGGCAUGCUUUUUGGCAUUAUGAAAAUAUUCUGGAAUUAGGUAGUGGUGAUGGUUGCAGAACUUUUGGAAUAUGGUAAAAGACACUGAAAUAUAUGCUUAAAAAUGGUGAUUUUUGUGAUAUAUGAAUUAUACUAUAGAACUAAUAAUAACAGUAAUAAAGCAAGGUGUCUUUCCACA